CCAGUGGAGUCUCCUUGAGUUGAGGAGAUGGAGGUGGGUGUCAAGGUGCGCCACAGUGGAUAGAGUUUGCAGGGCAGAGUACCAGAAACAAGGGAACAGCACAAUCACCAAAAAAAAGGCUCUGGAGAUAUGGAGAAGAUCCCCGAACUACGGCGACGAGGCCUGCCUGUGGCUCGCGUUGCUGAUGCCAUCCCUUACUGCUCCUCAGACUGGGCGCUUCUGAGGGAGGAAGAAAAGGAGAAAUACGCAGAAAUGGCUCGAGAAUGGAGGGCCGCUCAGGGAAAGGACCCUGGGCCCUCAGAGAAGCAGAAACCUGUUUUCACACCACUGAGGAGGCCAGGCAUGCUUGUACCAAAGCAGAAUGUUUCACCUCCAGAUAUGUCAGCUUUGUCUUUAAAAGGUGAUCAAGCUCUCCUUGGAGGCAUUUUUUAUUUUUUGAACAUUUUUAGCCAUGGCGAGCUACCUCCUCAUUGUGAACAGCGCUUCCUCCCUUGUGAAAUUGGCUGUGUUAAGUAUUCUCUCCAAGAAGGUAUUAUGGCAGAUUUCCACAGUUUUAUAAAUCCUGGUGAAAUUCCACGAGGAUUUCGAUUUCAUUGUCAGGCUGCAAGUGAUUCUAGUCACAAGAUUCCUAUUUCAAAUUUUGAACGUGGGCAUAACCAAGCAACUGUGUUACAAAACCUUUAUAGAUUUAUUCAUCCCAACCCAGGGAACUGGCCACCUAUCUACUGCAAGUCUGAUGAUAGAACCAGAGUCAACUGGUGUUUGAAGCAUAUGGCAAAGGCAUCAGAAAUCAGGCAAGAUCUACAACUUCUCACUGUAGAGGACCUUGUAGUGGGGAUCUACCAACAAAAAUUUCUCAAGGAGCCCUCUAAGACUUGGAUUCGAAGCCUCCUAGAUGUGGCCAUGUGGGAUUAUUCUAGCAACACAAGGUGCAAGUGGCAUGAAGAAAAUGAUAUUCUCUUCUGUGCUUUAGCUGUUUGCAAGAAGAUUGCGUACUGCAUCAGUAAUUCUCUGGCCACUCUCUUUGGAAUCCAGCUCACAGAGGCUCAUGUACCACUACAAGAUUAUGAGGCCAGCAAUAGUGUGACACCCAAAAUGGUUGUAUUGGAUGCAGGGCGUUACCAGAAGCUAAGGGUUGGGAGUUCAGGAUUCUCUCAUUUCAACUCUUCUAAUGAGGAACAAAGAUCAAACACACCCAUUGGUGACUACCCAUCUAGGGCAAAAAUUUCUGGCCAAAACAGCAGCGUUCGGGGAAGAGGAAUUACCCGCUUACUAGAGAGCAUUUCCAAUUCUUCCAGCAAUAUCCACAAAUUCUCCAACUGUGACACUUCACUCUCACCUUACAUGUCCCAAAAAGAUGGAUACAAAUCUUUCUCUUCCUUAUCUUAAUGAUGGUACUCUUUUCAAUUUCUGAAAACAGUAACAGGCCCAACUUCCUUCUUACUACAGUCAUAUUAAACAGAUCACAUCAAUGACAAAUGUCACUACUAUAAAAACUACUUAAUUUGUAAGGAAAUUGUUUCAUAGAUUUAAAAAAAUUGUGGUUGGAGAGCAUCUUGGCAUUUGUGCUUUUUUUCUUGAGGGAUUGUUCUGCUUCCUGGCUGUAUGAUGGGUAUAUCAUUAAAGUUUGGAGUCCUAUAUGAACAAAACUGACAUUUUUAGAGUUGUACUUUUGGGAAUGUUAUAGAUUGAUCAUUCUUUCUCCUGAUAAUAAAGGUAUUGAAUAUCUGUUAUGAAAGGUUCUAAAA